GCGUCUCUUGUUUGUGCGGCUGACCAGUUGGCGACAUGGUGGCACCCGUGCUGGAGACUUCUCACGUGUUUUGCUGCCCAAACCGGGUGCGGGGAGUCCUGAACUGGAGCUCUGGGCCCAGAGGACUUCUGGCCUUUGGCACGUCCUGCUCCGUGGUGCUCUAUGACCCCCUGAAAAGGGUUGUUGUUACCAACUUGAAUGGUCACACCGCCCGAGUCAAUUGCAUACAGUGGAUUUGUAAACAGGAUGGCUCCCCUUCUACUGAAUUAGUUUCUGGAGGAUCUGAUAAUCAAGUGAUUCACUGGGAAAUAGAGGAUAAUCAGCUUUUAAAAGCAGUGCAUCUUCAAGGCCAUGAAGGACCUGUUUAUGCGGUGCAUGCUGUUUACCAGAGGAGGACAUCAGAUCCUGCAUUAUGUACACUGAUCGUUUCUGCAGCUGCAGAUUCUGCUGUUCGACUCUGGUCUAAAAAGGGUCCAGAAGUAAUGUGCCUUCAGACUUUAAACUUUGGAAAUGGAUUUGCUUUGGCUCUCUGCUUAUCUUUUUUGCCAAAUACUGAUGUUACCUGGAAGACUGGCCAGGUGGAACGAGGCAGGGCCUGGAAGCCACCAGCCUCUCUCGCCCUCUGUAGCAGGAGCUGCGACUCUAUGGUUUCAUGUUACGCUUCCAUUCUGUGCAAGGCUCUGUGGAAGGAGAAGCUGCACACAUUCUGGCAUCAUAACAGAAUUUCAUUUCUUCCAUCUGCAUUCAGGCCAAUACCAAUAUUAGCAUGUGGCAAUGAUGAUUGCAGAAUUCACAUAUUUGCUCAACAAAAUGAUCAGUUUCAGAAAGUGCUUUCUCUCUGUGGACAUGAGGAUUGGAUUAGAGGAGUGGAAUGGGCAGCCUUUGGUAGAGAUCUUUUCCUAGCAAGCUGUUCACAAGAUUGCCUGAUAAGAAUAUGGAAGCUGUAUAUAAAGUCAACAUCUUUAGAAACUCAGGAUGACGAUAACAUAAGACUGAAAGAAAAUACUUUUACCAUAGAAAAUGAAAGUGUUAAAAUAGCAUUUGCUGUUACUCUGGAGACAGUGCUAGCCGGUCAUGAAAACUGGGUAAAUGCAGUUCACUGGCAACCUGUGUUUUACAAAGAUGGUGUCCUACAGCAGCCAGUGAGAUUAUUAUCUGCUUCCAUGGAUAAAACCAUGAUUCUCUGGGCUCCAGAUGAAGAGUCAGGAGUUUGGCUAGAACAGGUUCGAGUAGGUGAAGUAGGUGGGAAUACUUUGGGAUUUUAUGAUUGCCAGUUCAAUGAAGAUGGCUCCAUGAUCAUUGCUCAUGCUUUCCACGGAGCGUUGCACCUUUGGAAACAGAAUACAGUUAACCCAAGAGAGUGGACUCCAGAGAUUGUCAUUUCAGGACACUUUGAUGGUGUCCAAGACCUAGUCUGGGAUCCAGAAGGAGAAUUUAUUAUCACUGUUGGUACUGAUCAGACAACUAGACUUUUUGCUCCAUGGAAGAGAAAAGACCAAUCACAGGUGACUUGGCAUGAAAUUGCAAGGCCUCAGAUACAUGGGUAUGACCUGAAAUGUUUGGCAAUGAUUAAUCGGUUUCAGUUUGUAUCUGGAGCAGAUGAAAAAGUUCUUCGGGUUUUUUCUGCACCUCGGAAUUUUGUGGAAAAUUUUUGUGCCAUUACAGGACAAUCACUGAAUCAUGUGCUCUGUAAUCAAGAUAGUGAUCUUCCAGAAGGAGCCACUGUCCCUGCAUUGGGAUUAUCAAAUAAAGCUGUCUUUCAGGGAGAUAUAGCUUCUCAGCCUUCUGAUGAAGAGGAGCUGUUAACUAGUACUGGUUUUGAGUAUCAGCAGGUGGCCUUUCAGCCCUCCAUACUUACUGAGCCUCCCACUGAGGAUCAUCUUCUGCAGAAUACUUUGUGGCCUGAAGUUCAAAAACUAUAUGGGCACGGUUAUGAAAUAUUUUGUGUUACUUGUAACAGUUCAAAGACUCUGCUUGCCUCAGCUUGUAAGGCAGCUAAGAAAGAGCAUGCAGCUAUCAUUCUUUGGAACACUACAUCUUGGAAACAGGUGCAGAAUUUAGUUUUCCACAGUUUGACAGUCACGCAGAUGGCCUUCUCACCUAAUGAGAAGUUCUUACUAGCUGUUUCCAGAGAUCGAACCUGGUCAUUGUGGAAAAAGCAGGAUACAAUCUCACCUGAGUUCGAGCCAGUUUUUAGUCUUUUUGCCUUCACCAACAAAAUUACUUCUGUGCACAGUAGAAUUAUUUGGUCUUGUGAUUGGAGUCCUGACAGCAAGUAUUUCUUCACUGGGAGUCGAGACAAAAAGGUGGUUGUCUGGGGUGAGUGCGACUCCACUGAUGACUGUAUUGAGCACAACAUUGGCCCCUGCUCCUCAGUCCUGGACGUGGGUGGGGCUGUGACAGCUGUCAGCGUCUGCCCAGUGCUCCACCCUUCUCAACGAUACGUGGUUGCAGUAGGAUUGGAGUGUGGAAAGAUUUGCUUAUAUACCUGGAAAAAGACUGAUCAAGUUCCAGAAAUAAAUGACUGGACCCACUGUGUAGAAACAAGUCAAAGCCAAAGUCAUACACUGGCUAUCAGAAAAUUAUGCUGGAAGAAUUGCAGUGGAAAAACUGAACAGAAGGAAGCAGAAGGUGCUGAGUGGUUACACUUUGCAAGCUGUGGUGAAGAUCACACUGUGAAGAUACACAGAGUCAAUAAAUGUGCACUGUAAUGGACUUAAUAACUACAUGCUUGCAGUCACUGGUAUCUUAAAAUAUUAUCAUGUAAACAGGUCAUCUUUACCUUCAUAACUGAAUUGAGUUUCUGGGUUUUUUUUUUUUUUGAGAUGGAGUCUUGCUUUGUCACAACCUCCACCUCCCAGGUUCAAGCGAUUCUCUUUCUUCAGCCUCCUGAGUAGCUGGGACUAGAGGCACACCACCAAUUCCGGCUAAUUUUUGUAUUUUUAGUAGAGACUGGGUUUCACCGUUGGCCAGGCGGGUCUCAAACUCCUCGUCUCAGGUGAUCUGCUUGCCUCGGCCUCCCAAAGUGCUGGGAUUACAGGCGUGAGCCACUGCGCCCAGCCUGAGUUUCAUUUUUUAAGUCACAUAGCAGUAGUCCUUAUUUCAGUGCUAGACCCUUUGAAAUGCGAUGAAAGCUAUAUGGACCCUUCGCUUUGUUAUAUAACAUAUGCACACAUACCCAGAAUUUUGCACAUAUGUUCAGAGAUUCCUAGACCUGCAGACCUGCCUCUGUGUGUCCCAAUUUAAGAACCUCUGUUCUUUCUUCAUGACUGGAUUUGCCCAAUUUUGUGUUAUUUUGGGACUUAAUUUGUCCCUCUUUGGGACAUUUCCUUAUUUAUUGCCCUCUUCAGAGAGUAGAUGUAGAAAAUAAAGAGAGGAAACCUAGAUUACUUAAUUUUAUUUUAACAUUUUCUAUAGAUAGCAUACCACGCCAAGUGUGCUCUGUCUUGAUCCCCUUCUUUCUAGCAUCUGCCAGACAUUGUAGAGUUUCGCAAGCAGUUGUAGGUUUGAGCUGCAGCCAGUCAUUUCUUUUAUUCUUUAAAAGUACAUAGAUUUGUCUUUUUAGGGCUUUACUGAAAGUAAAAUAUCCUGACAUUUAAACUGACAGAUGUAGGAGGUAAAAAAUAGAGUUCUGAAACAUUUGAAUUUAUGUGACAGCUGAAGUCACGAGAUGAGGGAUAUAUGUCCCCCAGGGAGGAUGCAGAAAGAAGAAAAGGGUACUGGAAACAGCAUGUCAGUGGUGCCAGCUGAGGGCUGGAGGCAGCCAGGAGAGUUGGGAGCCUGGGUGCUGGGUGGAGAGAGGUUAACAGGGAAGACAUGGGAAGUAUUGUGAAGGCUGGUGUGAGCAGGGGACUACUCCAGCCCUGUUGGAACAUAGAGCCAUUUGGCAGAUUGACAAUGCAGUGACAGCUGUAUAUAAUAAAUGUGUUGAAAGGAGGAAGGUGAGGAUUUUCUUGGUGGGAGUUUAUGCUGUUAUUUAACAUAUUUUGCUUCCAAAGGGGUUAAGAUGUUUUACCUAAAUGGAGGUUUCUAGGUCAGUGCUAUACAAUAUUUCUAAUCUGUGUUUUAUAGUGUGAGCUACAUAUGUAAUUUUAAAAUUUUCAAGUAGCCACAUAAUAAAGGAAACAGGUGAAAUUUAAUGACAUAUUUCCUUUAAUACGGUAUAUCCAAAAUAUUAUUAUGUCAACCUAUAAUCAGUAUAAAAACCUGUUACUGAAAUAUUUUAUAGGGCCCAUCUCAGUUCAGACUAGCCACAUUUAAGUGCUUCAUAGCCACAUGUGGCUCAUGGCCAUCCAUAUUUGGACAAUGUACUUUAGACUAUUGCAUCUGUAUACUCUUGUGCCGUCAGCUGGGGGGUGGGGUGUGUGUGCGUGUAUACCAAGGCAGUGAGCAUCUGAGCUUUGAACCUCAAAGACCAAAAUGCCCUGCCCAUUUUCCUGCUUAUCAGCUGAGGAAUCUUUACCCACAUUGACACAUGGGCUUGUUCUGACCCAAGUGCAUGCAGGCUUCCAGAGCAGAUUCAGAGGCCUAACUUAGUCCUUUAGCUUUCCUCCCAGCACAGAACUCCCAAGGUUAUCUGCAAGUAGGCCUUGCCUAGAGAGACUGAGUUUUCAAGUUGUCAGUUUUCCCAAAUUGUCCUCAAGCAUCUUCCUCUGGAAUCACCUUACUGUUUAGUAAACAUUCAGAGGACUUGCUACACAUCUGGGCAGUCUGCAUUGUAAUUCAUAUGUGUUUACACAUUUGUGUCUUCAUCUGCUAAAGCACCUUUGAACCAUAUUGUAAUUCAUAAUAUCUGAAGCAAUUAUUAUGAAUUGUAGUAAUUCAUAAUAUUGAAGCGAUUCAUAAUAUCUGAAGCAAUCCCCAGAUACGGGUUAGGCAUGGCCCUGCUCUGAGCAGGAUGGCAAAAGUGGCAGUCCGUGACGCAGCCCUUGUUACCCCAGGCUAUUACUAAAUGGUGGUGGUGGUUUUAUCUUAAUUAAAAUGACAUCACCAACAAUGGGCCCUUUCCUGUCUGCCAGGAAAAGUUUUCUGUAGUGACGCACGUGUUGUGUGUGUAUGUGUGCGUUUGAGGCUAUAUUACUCAUUGCUACGGCAGUUCAAAAUGACUUGGAAAAAAACAAUGAACGCUGGUCAUUGAUAUGUAUACUGACAUGUUUGAGGGAAGUUACUGUGGUCUGUAACUUAUGAAAUACAUAAAAAAUAUGAUGGGUGGAGUGACGGACACAUGGACAGAUAUGAAGCAAGCACUGUAAAAUAUUAGUGGUAGUUUUUGUAUGCCCAUACUCACGGCACCAUUAUUCACAGUAGCUAAGAGAUGGAAGCAAUAUGUGCCCAUCAGUGGGUGAAUGAUCAACAAAAUGUGGUAUAUUCAUACAGUGGAAUAUUAUUCAGCCUCUAAAAGGAAGAUACGCUGACAUGUGCUGCAACAUGGAUGAAUCUUGAGGACAUGAUGCUAAGUGAAGUAAGCCAGUCACUGGAAGACAAAUACUCUAUGCUUCCAUUUAUGUGAAGUAUCUAGAGCAGUCAAAUGCAUAGAAACAAGUAGAAUGGUAGUUGCCAAGGACUGGGGGAGGAGGAAAUGAGGAGUUGUUUAAUGGGUAUAGUGUUUCAGUUUUGCAAGAUAAAAAGUCCUGUGGAUUGGUUGCACAGUUAAGUUAUGUGAAUGCUGUAUGCCAACUCAACUGUACACUCUAAAAUGGUUAAGAUGGUAAAUCUUAUCUUUAUUUUACCACAGUUUUUUUUAAAGCAUGGUAAACACCAUUUCCCAGGAUGUAAAUCGGUACUAAAAAAAAAGUGCUCCAAAGUAAGAUAUAUUUGGGAAACACAGGGAUAACUAAGGUUAGAUAGGUGUUCUUUAUUGCAGGAAUUCUAAGAGCAUUUAACAAAUUAAUUUACACUGGGAAUUUUCAGUGUGGAGGGUCUGGCUCAUAGCAUUUCACAAACAUUAUACUUCAGAGUCCCAAAGCCUUUAAAUAAAAUGUUAAUGGUAGAAACUCCUUAAGGGGUGUUCACUGUACAAUUCUUUCAACUUUUCUGCAUGCUGGGAGUUUUUUUGGUAACAACGUGUUGGGGAAAAUGGCCUUGGAAUAUUUCAUUCAAAUUGGAGCCAAGCUAACACAAAGCUGUUGCUGCUAGUGGGAACAGCCCUGAUGUCCAUGUAACAAGCUGCCCUCCCCAACUCCCUCCUUCCUGUUUCUCCCUCCUCGGCACCCACUUCUAGGAUUAACAGGCAGGGAGACGGGAGAGCCCAGCUCUGGGUACAGUUGGGCCACAGCAGAAGGAGGGCCAGGGUAGAGGUUUGGGCCUUGGCUCUGAUGCUUGAACAUAAACACACCUAGUCAGAAGUACAUCAGUACAAAGUGGGCCCUACAAAAUUAUAGGGUCAGAAAACAGGUAAGUGGUUACCAGGGGCUGGGAAUGGGGAGAGGAGUGACUACAGAGGGACCUAGAUUCUUCAACAAAUACAUUACAAGAGGAAAAGGGAAGGGAAGGGAAGCCUGGAGAUUGAAAGAUACUUGAGACGUGUGAAUCCAGUGCAAUGUAUGAACCUUGUUUGCCUCUUGAUCUGAACUAGCCAAUCAAUCUUGUAAAAAUGUGCUUAAGGGACAAAGCAAAUUUGAACUCUGGCUGGAUAUUUGAUGAUAUUAAGGAAACAACAUUUAAACAUAUGACAGUGGGGCUAUGGUUAUGAUUGGUUUUGUUUUUUUUUUCUCUAGAGACUGGGUUUUGCAGUGUUACCUAAGCUGGUCUUGAACUCCUGGGCUCAAGCAGUUCUCCCACCUCAGCCUUGGUUUAAGAAAAAAAAAAAAAAAGUUCUCUUGAAUCAUAAUUUCAGUAUUUAUGGAUGAAAUCAAUUUAUGUCUUGGGUUGUUUCAUAAUGAUUGUGUGUGUGUCAAGGACUAGAUGGGUUUUAGAUGUGUGGAUUAUUAAUGAAGCUGGGCAGUGUUGGGGUGGUCAUACUAUUCUAAUUUUUUAAUAUACUUAAAAUUUCCUUAUAAGAAUUGUUUAGAAAGAAUGAGCAUAUCCAUAAGUUAAAUACAAAAAUUGUUACAUUGUGAGGAGUUCUUCCCCUUCUAGCAUGUAGUGGAUGGUCCAGUAUUAAGGCUCUGCCAUGCUUAAACAAGAGACUGGCACUCCAAGGACAAUGAGGCUGAGGCCAGAAGAGAGACAGCGUGUUGGAUGGCUGCAUGUGGUUGGUGGAUAGAGGACUCUGAGCCCCACUCUGGUGGACUCAGAGAUCUGGGACCCGGGCCGGGCGUGGUGGCUCAUGCCUGUAAUCCCAGCAAUUUGGGAGGCUGAGGCGGGUGGAUCACUUGAGGUCAGGAGUUCGAGACCAGCCUGGCCAACAUGGUGAAACCCCAUCUCUACUAAAAAUACAAAAAAAAAAAAAAAAUUAGUCGGGCAUGGUGGUGGGCGCCUGUAAUCCCAGAUGUUCCAGAGGCUGAGGCAGGAGAACCGCUUGAACCCAGGAGGAGGAGGAGGUUGCAGUGGGCCGAGAUCGAGCCACUGCACUCCAGCCUGGGCAACAGAGUGAGACUCCAUCUCAAAAAAAAAAAAAAAAAAAAAAAAAAUCUGGGACCCAGUACUGAGUGAAGACACCAGAGUGAAGGAGAGAGGCCAUGCUGUGUCCGAGAAGCUCCUACUGGGGUGGAAGGGACAGCUCCACAAAGGCUGCUCUUGCAGGGGCUCUCCUGCAGCAAGGUGCCUGCUGACUGUCCCCAGACUGUCUCCCGACACAGAGGGAUGCAAAGGCAGCCUCUUCCUGCUCAGUGGAAUAGGGAAAUUAUAUCACCUUUCACUUCCCACUCUCACUUCUGCCCCUGCUACCCUUAGUCUUUGGCUUUUGCUGACAUUUUCCCCUCUUAUCUUUUCUCCUGACCAAGUUCUAGGUAUUUCAUAGGGCAGUCUAGGUGAGGGUUGGAACCCCAAUGAGUUGGGCAACAGAAACCCAGCUCACACUGGCUGUCACUGUGGGCAAGCUGUUCCCCUCAUCUCUAAAAGUGGAGAUGAGAUUAGUGUAUGAGUCUGGCUUCCAUUCAACUGUGUGUGAAAAAAAAUUGUAAAAUUUUCUUUCUGGUUUACGCAAGUUAAAAGUUUAUUUCUCUCAUAUGAAAGGAGUCAAGGCAGACAGACCAGGAUGGGGAGGGAGAUGUCUACAGGGUCAAGGACCCAGGCUCUUAUUUCGCUGUCUGACGUCCUUAGUAUGAGGCUUUCACCUUCCAGGAUGGCUGCUUGGCCUCCUGCCAUGGUCUUUGCGUUCCAGCCAGCAAAGAGGAAGAAGGCAUGAAGAAAGGCCUGCCCCUGACUUUAAAAACAUUUCUUGGAAGUCCCAUACUAUUUUGCUUAAUCUCCUCGGGCAGAAUUUAGUGUUGUGGCCAUACCGAGCUUCAGGAGAAGCUGGGAAAUUAAAUCUUUAUUGCAGAUGCCCAUGUGCUCAGCAGAGAACUGGGGUGCUUCAUUCUGGAAGAAAGGGAGAACAACAGUAACCAGUGUGUAGGAUUGUUCUGAGAAUUAAAUGAGCCAAUAUAUGAAAAACACUAGUUUGGUCCCUGGGAUAUAAAUAAGACAGCAGUAAUUUGUAUCUGGUACUAUUAUGAUUAAAUAAAGCUCUGCUCGUGUCAACUCCA